AGCAACCUGCUCUGGUUCCCUUCCACGCUGUGGAAGCUUUGUUCUUUUGGUCUUCAUGAUAAAUCUUGCUGCUGCUCACUCGUUGGGUCCGUGCCACCUUUAAGAGCUGUAACACUCACCGCGAAGGUCUGCAACUUCACUCCUGGGGCCAGCAAGACCACGAAUGCACCGAGAGGAAUGAACAACUCUGGACACACCAUCUUUAAGAACCGUAAUACUCACCGCAAGGGUCUGCAACUUCAUUCUUGAAGUCAGUGAGGCCAAGAACCCAUCAAUUCCGUACACAUUUUGGUGACUUUGAAGAGACUGUCACCUAUCACCAAGUGGUGAGACUAUUGCCAAGCAGUGAGACUAUUGCCAAGUGGUGAGACCAUCACCAAGCGGUGAGACUAUCACCUAUCGCCAAGUGGCCUGAUUCAGCAGGAAGCAUCUCAGACACCAACCACUAUGCUGUCAGCAGUUGCCCGGGGCUACCAGGGCUGGUUUCAUCCCUGUGCUAGGCUUUCUGUGAGGAUGAGCAGCACCGGGAUAGACAGGAAGGGCGUCCUGGCUAACCGGGUAGCCGUGGUCACGGGGUCCACCAGUGGGAUCGGCUUUGCCAUCGCCCGACGUCUGGCCCGGGACGGGGCCCACGUGGUCAUCAGCAGCCGGAAGCAGCAGAACGUGGACCGGGCCAUGGCCAAGCUGCAGGGGGAGGGGCUGAGUGUGGCGGGCAUUGUGUGCCACGUGGGGAAGGCUGAGGACCGGGAGCAGCUGGUGGCCAAGGCCCUGGAGCACUGUGGGGGCGUCGACUUCCUGGUGUGCAGCGCAGGGGUCAACCCUCUGGUAGGGAGCACUCUGGGGACCAGUGAGCAGAUCUGGGACAAGAUCCUAAGUGUGAACGUGAAGUCCCCAGCCCUGCUGCUGAGCCAGUUGCUGCCCUACAUGGAGAACAGGAGGGGUGCUGUCAUCCUGGUCUCUUCCAUUGCAGCUUAUAAUCCAGUAGUGGCGCUGGGUGUCUACAAUGUCAGCAAGACAGCGCUGCUGGGUCUCACUAGAACACUGGCAUUGGAGCUGGCCCCCAAGGACAUCCGGGUAAACUGCGUGGUUCCAGGAAUUAUCAAAACUGACUUCAGCAAAGUGGUGAGGAUUGGUUUCAUGGGAAUGAGUCUCUCUGGAAGAACUUCAAGGAACAUCAUCAGCUGCAGAGGAUUGGGGAGUCAGAGGACUGUGCAGGAAUCGUGUCCUUCCUGUGCUCUCCAGAUGCCAGCUACGUCAACGGGGAGAACAUUGCGGUGGCAGGCUACUCCACUCGGCUCUGAGAGGAGUGGGGGCGGCUGCGUAGCUGUGGUCCCAGGCCCAGGAGCCUGAGGGGGUGUCUAGGUGAUCAUUUGGAUCUGGAGGCAGAGUCUGCCAUUCUGCCAGACUAGCAAUUUGGGGGCUUACUCAUGCUAGGCUUGAGGAAGAAGAAAAACGCUUCGGCAUUCUCCUUAGGACUUAUCUGCUUGUAGAUUUGGCUGAUCCAAUUAACAUGUGGGGUUCUUGGUGUGGGUCUGGGGAGCUGAAGGAUUUUAUGGAGCUGGUGCUUUGGAGGAAUCUUAAGGGAAAGGAGUAGAAGCUCAGGCCUUUGAAGGAUUUCAGCUCCUCCUCUCUGUAAUUUGUGCUUUAAGCAUUUUUUUUCCUAAAAUAAACUCAAAUUUAUCCUCAA